AUGGAAAACCAAUCCAGCAUUUCUGAAUUUUUCCUCCGAGGAAUAUCAGCGCCUCCAGAGCAACAGCAGUCCCUCUUCGGAAUUUUCCUGUGUAUGUAUCUUGUCACCUUGACUGGGAACCUGCUCAUCAUCCUGGCCAUUGGCUCUGACCUGCACCUCCACACCCCCAUGUACUUUUUCUUGGCCAACCUGUCUUUUGUUGACAUGGGUUUAACGUCCUCCACAGUUACCAAGAUGCUGGUGAAUAUACAGACUCGGCAUCACACCAUCUCCUAUACGGGUUGCCUCACGCAAAUGUAUUUCUUUCUGAUGUUUGGUGAUCUAGACAGCUUCUUCCUGGCUGCCAUGGCGUAUGACCGCUAUGUGGCCAUUUGCCACCCCCUCUGCUACUCCACAGUCAUGAGGCCCCAAGUCUGUGCCCUAAUGCUUGCAUUGUGCUGGGUCCUCACCAAUAUCGUUGCCCUGACUCACACGUUCCUCAUGGCUCGGUUGUCCUUCUGUGUGACUGGGGAAAUUGCUCACUUUUUCUGUGACAUCACUCCUGUCCUGAAGCUGUCAUGUUCUGACACCCACAUCAACGAGAUGAUGGUUUUUGUCUUGGGAGGCACCGUACUCAUCGUCCCCUUUUUAUGCAUUGUCACCUCCUACAUCCACAUUGUGCCAGCUAUCCUGAGGGUCCGAACCCGUGGUGGGGUGGGCAAGGCCUUUUCCACCUGCAGUUCCCACCUCUGCGUUGUUUGUGUGUUCUAUGGGACCCUCUUCAGUGCCUACCUGUGUCCUCCCUCCAUUGCCUCUGAAGAGAAGGACAUUGCAGCAGCUGCAAUGUACACCAUAGUGACUCCCAUGUUGAACCCCUUUAUCUAUAGCCUAAGGAACAAGGACAUGAAGGGGGCCCUAAAGAGGCUCUUCAGUCACAGGAGUAUUGUUUCCUCUUAG